GUGACCUGCUCUGUUCCUUCCCUGCUGACCUGGGUACAGUCAUUACCUGGUGGGCAGGGCUAGCCUCUGGGCAGGUGCCGAGGAGGGUCAUCCCUGAGCACUCACCAGGUGCCUGUUCUGCACUGACCUGGUGGACUCUGUGGGGUGGGUGCUGUCCCCGAAUGUACCCAUUCCACAAGUGAGAUGUCUAGGGUCAGAGAGGAGGUGACUGGCCAAGAGACCCAGAUGUGAUCCUGGGCUGUGCUCUCAGCCCUGCCCUGUGCAUGCCCUGGUCUCUAUGGCCCUAGAUUCCAAAUCUGCCCAGGGUUUUCUGGCCCCUGAUGGGGCAGAGUCUGGCCCUGAAAGAGCUACUGGGAUGGAACUCCUAUGGGUGUGGUGGAGGGAGGUGGUGCUCGGUCCAAGUCUGUGCCCUAAGCUGGGUGUCCGCAGGAGGAGGUCUCACCAACUCAGACUUCACGUGCGGUCACUGAGGGUCUCCGUGGGACCCACUGGACACAUGGGGUCCCUUGUCUGGGAGUAGGGAGCCCUCUGCCUGUGGGCAGUUGUGGUAGAGGACCUUGAACACUGCUGCUCUGGGGCCUGGGCAGGGAGGACUUGGACAGUGGGGACCUGGUCAGGAAGGCCUGGUCACUGGGGGACUGGUCAGCGAGGACAUGGUCAGUGGGGAAUUGGUCAUCAGGGGCCUGGUCAGCAGAGGCUUGGCCACUGGGGCUUAGUCAGUGAAAAACUGGUCAGUGGGGACAUGGUCAGUUGGAGCCUGGUCAUCAGGGGCCUGAUCAGUGAGGACCUAGUCAGAAGGCCUGGUCACUGGGAAAACGGUCAGUGAAAGCCUGGCCGGCAGGGGUCUGGUUAGUGGGGGCCUGGCCAGAUGGUUGCUUGGUGACCUCAGGCACGGGGUUUGUCCUUAGAGCCUCCUUGCCUCCGUCCAUAGCAGAAAUGAGUCAUGGCACCCUGGAAGGCUACUGGGAGGAGGAGGUGAAAAAAUGUGUGGAAUCCGACCUUGCCACUCACACCCAGCAUUUUACAGUCUAGCUGAGUUCCCCCUAAUGAGGGGCCCUGUCCUGUGCCCUCUAACCCCUAGCCCCCAUCUGCAUCUUCAGGACUGCCCCGUGUGGGGAGUUCUGAGGUUGGGGAGGACCCAUGGAUGCUCUGAUGCUUGCCACAGGCCUCAAGGGAAGGUGACGCUGAUUAAGACUUGAUGAGCACUUGGGUGCACAUGUAAGUGGGACAGCCAGCCCUGGCCAGAGACGCUACUCGUGCACACACAUGUUCACCCACAUAAACAUACAUGCUCACCUGCACAAACACAUUUUGACACCUUAGGGGCUGGAGGACACCGACUCUGGGCCCUCUUGACCUGGGCAAUGGCCCAUUAUGAUGGGUGCCAUGACCUCAAAAUGUCACUGGUGCUGAGUGACCGCCCACCUGCCCACCCACUCACCUCUGUGUUGUGCAGCACUUGCACAUAAGACGCACACAGGUGUCUGGUUCUGUGGUGCAUGAACGACUUUUCUAAGCGAGAGACACAGCAGCCUGAGCAGACUCAGAGACUCUGUGGCGAUGGGUGCUGUCCCCAAAUGUAGCCAUUCCACAGGAAAACAAAGUCCCCUCCUGUAUUGACAGCUGGGAAUUGUGGUGUCCACCGUCCUCGACCUGCGACGGGGUCUCCAUGAGCACAGAGGCUGCUCUGGAGUCAACAGAUCAUCUUUUCCCCAAACCAAACUGCUUGGCUGGCGUUGUUCCUGAAGGGGCUUCACUGGCCAGAAGACAUCCAGUCCCUGACUCCACCUGCCUCCAGGUGCCCAGAACAGCCCAUCGUGGGGACUUCACCCUCAGCAAGUGGACGCCGUUUGUCCUGCCAGGGCAGGGACACCGAGCUGGGGCAGCAGUGGACUUGGGGCAUGAGCAGGUUGAUGUCAGAAAAUACACCAAUAACCUCGGGAUUGUGCAUGAGAUGGAGCUGCCCCGCGUCAGUGCCCUGGAGGUGAAGCAAAGACGCAAGGAAAGUAAACGUACCAACAAGUGGCAAAAGAUGCUUGCAGACUGGACAAAAUAUAGGAGCACCAAGAAGCUGUCUCAAAGAGUAUGCAAAGUCAUUCCCCUGGCGGUGCGGGGCCGGGCGUUGUCACUUUUGCUAGAUAUUGACAAAAUCAAGUCCCAGAACCCAGGCAAAUAUAAGGUCAUGAAGGAGAAGGGCAAGAGGUCCUCCAGAAUCAUCCACUGCAUCCAGCUAGAUGUCAGCCACACCCUGCAGAAACACAUGAUGUUCAUACAAAGAUUCGGAGUCAAGCAGCAGGAAUUAUGUGACAUCCUCGUGGCCUAUUCUGCAUAUAACCCUGCAGCCCUUGGGCUGUUGCAGGACCGUGGCCAGUUCUUGGUAUUGCUCAAGUCCCCUGGGCCUUCAGACUGGCGGGUGACUUCAAGGGAGCAACCAUCCUGGGCCUCUCCUGGGACAAACACUUGCCUUCACCCACUAUCGAUGUCUUGCUCAGCCCUCAGAGGAGCGUGGUUGGCGUGGAUUACUUCAUGCCUUGAUUCUGCCUUCCCGGAAACCACGGUGGCAGCAGGCUUGGAUGUCACCAAGUCACCGUGUUUCAUGCUAUUUCUGGAGGUUCUCGCCUUUGUGGCCUCGGAAAGGAAGGCGAUCUGGUGCUUUGGGGAAAGCCCUCGGGAUGCUCCUCCAGAUGGUCUUCUUCAGGCCUUUUGCUCAGCAUUGGUCUGAUCAGUUCUGCCAGCUCUGGGCCAUGAUCUCUUGGCACUGGCGCGGCUUUCCUUCAAUAAUUCCAUAAACUCCAGACUUCGUGUCUUUUGCAUGGAAAGCACGCGGUGCCCAUUUCAUCGACACCGCACCCCGGAGUCCAAACGUCAGCCCUGCGGGUGUUGGGUUUGUUAGGGACAAUUUCGGGCUCAGGUGCAGGGGGCGCUUCCCCAGCGCGGGCGCUUCCUGGGCCCCAUCUGAGGCCGUGGGCUCCUGGCAGGAGGACCUGGAGUUUUCAGAUCCCCGGGAAGGAUGCAUUUCCCCCACUCUCGGGCACAAGCUGCCCUUUGCUGGCGUUGGGCACGGAUCAUGGCCUCGCAGAAGCCCGCGACAGCGUGGAGCAGGUGGUGCCCCCGCCCGGGACUCCUGGUGGGUGAUGGCUCCGGGAGGCCUUGGCUGGGACAGAGUGGGGCCUCCGGGUCGGUCAGCGGCCCGAGCCCGGCUGCGGCUCUCGGAGGCUUGGGUUUGGAAGACACCGCCUGCCAUCCCGCGGCGCCUCUCGGGGUCCGCUCCCCCGGACUGGCCCUGCCCACCGCGCGCGAGUAGUAGCGGGCGGCCAGGAGUCAGUGGCAGGCGCGGCCGGUGGGAUGCCGGGUAGGAGGCUGCGCUGGAGCCCGCUGGGCAGCGCCGACCCCUAAGGCAGCCGGGCGGGUGAGCGAGCAGAGGCGUGGGCGGCUGAGGGGCUGAGGGGCUGAGGCGGCUGAGGCGGCUGAGGGGCUGAGGAGGCUGAGGGGCUGAGGGGCUGAGGCGGCUGAGGGGCUGAGGGGCUGAGGGGCGGGCAGCCUGGCCGGUCCCUGCCGCAGGGUCCACCGCACGUCACGUGGCCGAAUCCCUCGGGCUGCUUUCUCUCUGGGCUGUUUUCUUACUGUGAACCUCGUGGGCUCCUGCUCGGUGUCCUUUCUUACUCUGUCUCUGUUUUUGCAUUCUAUUGGCAAGUAUUUUAUUUAGGAUAUUUUACUGAUAUAACUGAGGAUGAACUGUGUUUUGCAGCAUUUUGUUUUAUUACGCGUUUUCUCCUAGAUUUUGGUAUCAUUUUUAUGCUGACUUGAUUAAACAUUUUGGAAACUUUCCUGGAACUGAUAGCUUUUAUAUGAUCUUUUUCUUGAGGUAAUAAAAUAAUUUACUUUGAAAUGUCUCAGCCUAACAACUUUUGUGCUUUUGUUGUUUUGUGCAGAGGUGGGAAGACUCCUUUGCAUUUUUGGUAUCACUUCUGUGUUAAUGAUUUUGUUGUUUGUUUCGCAAAAUCACUUAGUGAUCCGUGUUUUCCAACUUAAGAGUUAACAUGUACCAUUUUGUGAAAUAAAAAAAGUCUCGUAUA